GAUUAGUCCUACUUUGACAGCGGUGGAAACUGAAGCAGAGAGGUUCUCCAACUUGUCUGAGGUCCAAGAAGGAGCUGGUGACAGAGACCAGAUACCGGACCAGCACUUGGGUUUUCUGACUCACGGUUCUGGGCUCACCCCUCUCUGAGCAUGCACUGAGCCUGCUCUUGCAGGUUUCUUUAUCACAGGGAUCUAUCUACACGGUACUUUCUGCUCUCAGCUUUUUACAGUGGUGUAGAGUGCAGUGCAGCUGAAACCAGGUUAGUUGAUCUUAUGGUGUCAUCUAGAAAAACAAGAGAUGCAGAUUCUGGGUCACGAAGGCACAGUGCCCACUUGUUCCGUGGCACAGCCCCAGAGCUCCUGUUGAAGGAACAGACUCCAGGACUGACUUUCCACUUGAUUUUCGGAGCUCGCACAUCCCGAGAGAUUCAUGUUCAAGCUGCAUUUUAGACAUAGCUGGCAAGAGUAUUUUCGUGACCACAGCCAGCAGAGGAGAACUAAUGGGCAGAGACAACACUGAUCUGCUGCCAUCUGCACUGGGCAAGAUGGCCUCACCUGACUCACAGCUGUUGCUUUCUCUCGCGAAGCUUCUACCAUUUUCUGCUGAUUCUUAAAAUAGAUUUGGAUCUUGUCAAUUUUGGUCGUCAAAAAGAUUGAACUUUUACAGGAUGAAAUCCAUUAUUUUCCUAAAUUAUCUCGUUUUGGGAAAUCAGUUCUCGGCCAUAAGUGCAGGCUCAGGUGUGCUAAGGAGGGCACCCCAGACACCUGUGCUGCUCUUUGACAGGACUUACCUGUCAAAGGCGAAAAUAAGGGUGAUGUCAUGUGAGUUUUCCAUUAAGCUAAAUUUAUUCCAUGUACAGGACUAUCUUUUAUUCUGAAAUUGUCUUCUUGUUCCCUAUAACCUCAUAUUGGAAGUGAGAUACUGUCUUUUUGGGUAUUAAAAUGUCUUUUUUGUAGGAUCUUUUUUUUACUGAUCUUAUUUGUAUGUUAGGAUGAUAGCCCAGUGUCAGUCCUCAGGAUUCUUUAUGAAAUGUUCCUAGUCUGUGAAAUUCUAACUCUACAAUUUCAGUUUAGACCACAAAUCCCAGAUUUUUACCUUGUUUACAUUUGUAGUUACCACAUAAUAUUGCAAAUGAUUUAUGUAACCUCAAAGCCCAUUUUUUUAUUCUUUUCAUGUAAAAUGUCCAGAAUAGGCAAAUCCAUAGAGACAGAAAGCAGAUUAGAGGUUGCCAGGGGCUGCGGGGAGGGAGGAAGGGGGAGUAGUUACUUACAGGGAUGGGGAGUUCUUCUAGGAUCAUGAAAAAGGUUUGAAACUCGACAGAGGGCUGAUUGCACAACAUUGUAAAUGCACUAAAUGCCCCUGAAGUGUACUUGAAGUGGUUCAUUGUAUGUUAUAUGAAUUUUCCAUUUUUUUGAAAAGCCCAUUUUAUUCAGUGAUAUAAUGAUAUAUAAGAAGACCUGAAGGUGUAGGGGGAGUGUCGUAUUCAGAGGAUAUACAUCAAGGCAAGGAUACUCUGUAUGCUUGUACACACACACAAAUACAUAUACACAAAGAACAUACCUAUUAUUAAUUUCUGUUUCUAAGUAUGAUCAUUAGAAGCUGAUUAGGUAAAUAAACUUUCUGCUUUGGGACAAGCAGAAAGAUUUAAUUAACACUUAACUGAAAUUCACAGAUACUCUUUUUUUUUUUUUUUUUUUUAGACAGUGUCUCACUCUGCCUCCCAGGCUGGAGUACAGUGACACGAUCUCGGCUCACUGCAACCUCCGCCUCCUGGGUUCAAGCAAUUCUCUUACCUCAGCCUCCCGAGCAACUGAGACUACAGGCGUGUGCUACCAUGCCUGGUUAAUUUUUUGUAUUUUUAAUAGAGACGGGGUUUCAUUAUGCUGGCCAGGCUGUUCUCAAAUUCCUGGCCUCAAGUGAUCCACCCGCCUCGGCUUCUCAAAGUGCUGAGAGUACAGGCGCAAGCCACCGUGCCCAGCCUCAAAAGAUAUUCUUUUUCUUACCUCAAAAACUAUGUUUUCCAACUUUUCACAGUGGAAAGUUGAAGUCGUGAAAAUAUCCUCAGGAUAAAUCUGAAUCGUGUUUCUUUUAUUGCUGAGUCUGGUUGGCGUGUUCCUGGUAUUUAGUGGAACUCUGGUCAACACAGGCUGAAGUUAGUGGGGUUCUCUCUGUGGGGUUCUAACCUUGAAAUAGGAGCAUGGGGCUUGCCUUCCCCUUCUCCAUUCCUCCAAGAAAGAGAAAGGAAAGGAAGAGAAAAGAAAAAGCAUCCUGUAUUAUGUGUAAGUUUGUAAGAAUCCUUACUAUGAGUUCUGAGUACAACAUCUUUUUAACUCUUUUCUCUCCCUCUCCUGCUUCCUUCUUCAAUCUCCAGCUACCAUUCAUUUCCUGAUUUCAUUUAUAGGUCUUACCAGGCAAGAAGGCCAAGCAGAAGGAACCUACAUCAGGGAAGUGCUGGGCUACGGGCCCCACCUGGACUUGGGGUUCUGGGCAGCCUGAACACAGGUUUCUUAGUUUCCUGAAGUAAUUGAGCUUGUUGCCUUAACUUCAGUUAAAACACUGAUCGUGCUUUACUUUUAACUGAGCAUUGAGACCUCUUAUAAUAUUCCAUAAGGCUGGAUAUUGUUUUGAGGAAGACGAUUUUUCCUCUUAACCUUGCCUCUGUGUUUGUGUGUGUGUUUGGUCGGUGUUUAGACAGUUUUCCAUGCAUGGACCCUGAUUACAGCGGGAGCAGGCAACGUGAGGUGCCCGCAAUCAGACAUCCAGCUCCACAUGGUGGCCUCCCUGCCCCCAGCUCAUCCUUACGCAGUGCCUUCAAAUUGAGUGUCUUCAAAGAUUGCAAAUGCACAAGAUUCGAGACCUAUGUAUACAGAGGGCCAACUUUUCAUACGCACGGGUUCUGCGGGCCGACUGUGGGACUUGAAUAUGCGUGGAUUUGGAUGUUCCUCCUGCUGAUCAAGAGAAGCUUUUUAUCCAGAAGUUACGUCAGUGUUGCGUCCUCUUUGACUUUGUUUCUGAUCCACUAAGUGACCUAAAGUGGAAGGAAGUAAAACGAGCUGCUUUAAGUGAAAUGGUAGAAUAUAUCACCCAUAAUCGGAAUGUGAUCACAGAGCCUAUUUACCCAGAAGUAGUCCAUAUGUUUGCAGUUAACAUGUUUCGAACAUUACCACCUUCCUCCAAUCCUACGGGAGCGGAAUUUGACCCGGAGGAAGAUGAACCAACGUUAGAAGCAGCCUGGCCUCAUCUACAGCUUGUUUAUGAAUUUUUCUUAAGAUUUUUAGAGUCUCCAGAUUUCCAACCUAAUAUAGCGAAGAAAUAUAUUGAUCAGAAGUUUGUAUUGCAGCUUUUAGAGCUCUUUGACAGUGAAGAUCCUCGGGAGAGAGAUUUUCUUAAAACCACCCUUCACAGAAUCUAUGGGAAAUUCCUAGGCUUGAGAGCUUACAUCAGAAAACAGAUAAAUAAUAUAUUUUAUAGGUUUAUUUAUGAAACAGAGCAUCAUAAUGGCAUAGCAGAGUUACUGGAAAUAUUGGGAAGUAUAAUUAAUGGAUUUGCCUUACCACUAAAAGAAGAGCACAAGAUUUUCUUAUUGAAGGUGUUACUACCUUUGCACAAAGUGAAAUCUCUGAGUGUCUACCAUCCCCAGCUGGCAUACUGUGUAGUGCAGUUUUUAGAAAAGGACAGCACCCUCACGGAACCAGUGGUGAUGGCACUUCUCAAAUACUGGCCAAAGACUCACAGUCCAAAAGAAGUAAUGUUCUUAAACGAAUUAGAAGAGAUUUUAGAUGUCAUUGAACCAUCAGAAUUUGUGAAGAUCAUGGAACCCCUCUUCCGGCAGUUGGCCAAAUGUGUCUCCAGCCCACACUUCCAGGUGGCAGAGCGAGCUCUCUAUUACUGGAAUAAUGAAUACAUCAUGAGUUUAAUCAGUGACAACGCAGCGAAGAUUCUGCCCAUCAUGUUUCCUUCCUUGUACCGCAACUCAAAGACCCAUUGGAACAAGACAAUACAUGGCUUGAUAUACAACGCCCUGAAGCUCUUCAUGGAGAUGAACCAAAAGCUAUUUGAUGACUGUACACAACAGUUCAAAGCAGAGAAACUAAAAGAGAAGCUAAAAAUGAAAGAACGGGAAGAAGCAUGGGUUAAAAUAGAAAAUCUAGCCAAAGCCAAUCCCCAGUACACAGUGUAUAGUCAAGCCAGCACCAUGAGCAUUCCGGUUGCAAUGGAGACAGAUGGGCCUUUAUUUGAAGAUGUGCAGAUGCUGAGAAAGACAGUGAAGGACGAGGCUCAUCAGGCACAGAAAGAUCCGAAGAAGGACCGUCCUCUUGCACGCCGCAAGUCCGAGCUGCCUCAGGACCCCCACACCAAGAAAGCCUUGGAAGCUCACUGCAGGGCCGAUGAGCUGGCCUCCCAGGACGGCCGCUAGCCUCCGGGGCGCCGCGUCGGGGCCGGGCCCGCCAGUUCUUUUCCGGAUUCUGUAGAAAAUACAUACUUCCUGUGCCAUACCAAUCAGUUACACUCAAAGCUUUCUUGGACCCCGUUCCGUAGGCAAUAACGUGCGUCCGCCUCAGCGCGAGAUUAGGAGUUCAAACAAUGGUGACUUCCCAGAGCCCGCUGGCAGAGCCGCGGGUUGACGACGGUGUCCUCGCAGUGUCGCCGCCACCCCAGCGUAGUCCAAGUCAGACUAUUUCACAAAGUCAGAGCGAUAGGAAAGCACCCUGCCCUUCAUCUUCAUGUUCUCCCAAAUGGAACUUAGGAUCUUUUAACAUAGGUGGUUCUGUGAUAACAUCAGUGUUUUCCAAAUCAAAGGAACGCUUUAAAAAAUAGGACCUAUUUUUUAAGACUUUACAGCCUUUGAAAUGGUUUCCACGUGAUUGUUACGCCAGCAGUUCUCGUUUUGUUUGUUUUUCAAUCUCAGUGAAAUGGCUCUUUGCUUUCGAGUUCUCACGCAACGUACUGGGCAAAUGACAAUCCUCAGCCGCUGGUAUUUUCUAAGGGGUCUCUUCACUUUGAUGAGUGACAUGAACACCGUGUCUCCUUCUCUUGUGUGUACCUAAAGCCAUAUUUCCAAGUCUGUGGUACUCCAGGAUUCCAGGAGUAAGCCUGUAGAAGAGAUUUAUUUUAAAAGAGAUUGCUCUGAAAUUUAUCUUAAAAGAGCUUGCUCUGUCUACCUUGACAGAAAUUGGAGUUUUAAAAUUAUGUGUUAAUAUUUUUAUUUGCAGAUUUCGUUUCCGUCAACUUAAACAUUGUUGCCCUUCAACAAGGCUCUUGAAUUAAUAAAAUUAUAGUCUCUAAGAAUUCCACAUUUUAUGGAAAGUUAGAGCAAAAUCAUUUUGAGUUAAGCCAGUUCUUAGCCUAAUGCAAACUGCAGCGCCUUUAAGCAUAAAGUAACACAACAGCAUUGCACGGGGCCGGCACUGCCGCUGCCUUCACUGAAGGCUGCAGUGCUGUUCUGAGAGCUUGGAGGAGGCACCAGCGAGGAUGACGUUUAGUGGAGCUCUUUCUGUUGAAAAGAGCUCACGUUAUCAACACCUUGUAAGGAAAAUACAGUGUCUGAGUUUUCAUCGGUCUUCACAUGCUGCUAUAUAUUCCACAGAGUUCCUUGCAUGUACUGAGCUUUUGUUUUAGAUGGAAUAGCACAAGGAGAAAAAUCUUUAAACUUAGUGCUUUGUCUAUUCUUUAUUUCUCUCAGGGUGGCCAGUAUUUUGACUUAUUUAUCCUGCUUGAAAGCUACUUGAGAUGUGUACUGCUAUUCUAAACACGUGAUCUAGUUUCUUUCAUCUCUGGCAUAAGAUUAUAUAACUUAAUGUUAAGUGUCUUGAGGCAUAAAAGACAAAAUGUGGCUUAUUUUAGGAUCUGUUUUUUCAUCGAGGUCUCGGGUAUCCUUUCAAAGAUAGUGAGAAGCAGACACUGCUCCUUGUGCAGCUCUGGUACCUCCUGCCCACUGCUGUCACUUCAAGCCACUGGCAAUGCUUCUGUCCUCGUGUCUUGGAGGAAAAUCACCUGGGGGGAGGGGACUUCUUGUGGUAAGAGCAAGUGCAGGUAUGAAAUGCGAAGAUUGCCCCAGCUAAAAGUGGACAAGUCCGCUUUGUGAGAUGAAUACUUCCUGAGAAACUUGACAAGUAUCUCUCCAUUUUACCAUUAUGAAAACUAUCAUUAAAAAAAACAGUUUAGAUGCCUUCUCCUUUUGAGGGAAAAAGGGUGCUUUUUAUUGUAUAAAGCAGCGUCUUAUGUAUUUUGAUAUACCAUUGUUUGAACUUCCGUCUUUAGCUGAUAGAUUCUCAAAUAUCCUUGAUUUUGGAUGUUCAGUAUGUUUGUGAGAGAGGUUUCUGGGAAGACUCUCUUUUUGCCCUCGGGAAAAAGCAAAAUAUCAAUGUUUGGGUGACUGUGUAAAGCUCAGUGUGUAAGAACAUCUUUUUGUCUAGGUUUUCUUUCUGCUCUUUAUUGAAGACAAACACUCACCAAAAAGAAAAAUAAAAGUUUUCAGAGAAACUAAUUUUCUUUGGCAAGAGUAUUACUUAAUAUUUUGGCCUCCUAAAGUUUCCCUAGUUAGUACUCGGACUCCUGUGCUAAUUGUCAGCUUACAUAUCAUUGUAUAGAGACUGUUUAUUCUGUACCAAACUGAUUUCAAAAGUACUACAUUGAAAAUAAACCGGUGACUGUUUUUCUUCAUAAAGUUCUGCGUUUGGCAUCUUCACUCUUUCCAAAAUGUAUCUGUACAUCAGAAAUGUCACUAUUCCAAGUGUCUUUUUAGUGUGGCUUUAGUAUGGCUUCCUUUUAAUAUUGUACAUACAUUGUAUCUUUGUUUUAUGGUAAUAAGUAAUAAAAAUGUAGACUUCAUAUUUUGUACAAAAUGUCCUAUGUACAGAAUAAAAAAGUUCAUAGAAACAGCAAAUAUAGGUAAGUGGCACAAUUAUUUUUCUUUAGAAAAUAUCUGUAACUUUAUGCAUUAGUGAAAUGUUAAGUACCGACAUAUUUUUUAACAUUUUGUAAUUCAAAACUUUUUGUUUUGACAUUGUUUAUGAAGAGAAACUUCAUACACUUGCCAUUUAAUAUGCUCUUUUAUCUAAUUUUCAAAAACUCUAAAAAACGGUGUAUCAUAUGGACUAAAUAAAGAACAUGUGAAUUUUAUUGCUCAUCAUGAAA